GCGACAGAGUGAGACUGUCACAAAACAAAACAAAACUCUGAUGGAGUUGUGCAAGCAGAUUAAUGUUUUUUGUUUUGUUUUUUGAGACGGAGUCUCGCUGUGCUACCCAGGCUGGAGUGCAGUGGUGCAAUCUUGGCUCACUGCAACCUCUGCCUCCUGGGUUUAAGCGAUUCUCCUGCCUCAGCCUCUUGAGUAGCUGGGAUUACAGGUGCCCGCCACCACGCCGAGCUAAUUUUUGUAUUUUUAAUGGAGACUGGGUUUCACUAUGUUGGCCAGGCUGGUCUCGAACUCCUGACCUCAGGUUAUCCGCCCGCCUUGGCCUCCCAAAGUGUUGGGAUUACAGGCGUGAGCCACUGCUCCCAGCCUCCAUCAGUUUUUGGAUGACCAGGUAUAUUGUUAGUGAGCAGUAAUAUUUUCAAAGGAAUCUUUUUUUUCUGAGCAGUAGGUCUCAACAGUGAGCUUAAAUAGUCAACCACGCUGUAAACAGAUGUGCUGUCAUCCAAGCUUUGCUCCAUUUAUAGAGCACAGGCAGAGUAGAUUUUGUAUAAUUCUUAAGGGCCCUAGAAUUUUUGGAAUGGUAAAUGAGCAUCGGCUUCCACAGGCAUUGACUUCUUUGUAGCUAUGAAAGUCCUUGAUGGCAUCUUCUUCCAGUAAAAGUCCAUUUUGUCUGCACUGAAAUUCUGUUGUUUAAUGUAGCCAGUUGCAUCAAUUACUCUAGCUAGAUCUUCGGGAUAAAACUUGCUGCAGCUUCUACAUUAGCACUUGCUACUUCACCUUAUACUUUUAUGUUAUGGAGAUGGCUUCUUUGCUUAAACCUCAUGAACCAACUUUUCUUCUGCAGCCCCCUCACCUCUCUCAGCCUUCAUAGAAUUGAGAGUUAGGGCAUUGCUCCACAUUAGGCUUUGGCUUAAAGGAAUGUUGUGGUUGGUUUGAUCUUCUGUCUAGACCACUGAAACUUUCUUCAUAUCAGCAAUAAAGCUGUUUGCUUUCUUAUUUGUGUGUUCACUGGAGGAGCACUUUUAAUUUCCUUCAAGAACUUUUUCUUUGCAGUCACAGCUUGGGUAAGUGUUUGGUGCAAGAGGCCUAGCUCUUGGUCCAUCUCAGCUCUUUUUUUUUUUUUUGAACCGGAGUCUUGCACUGUCGCCCAGGCUGGAGUGCAAUGGUACGAUCUCAGCUGACUGCAACCUUCGCCUCCUGGGUUCAAGAGAUUCUUCUGCCUCAGCUUCCCAAGUAGCUGGGAUUACAGGCGCCCACUACCAUGCCUGGCUAAUUUUUGUAUUUUUGGUAGAGAAGGGGUUUCAUCAUGUUGGUCAGGGUGGUCUUGAACUCCUGACCUCAGGUGAUCCACCCGCCUCGGCCUCCCAAAGUGCUGGGAUUACAGGCAUGAGCCACCGCGCCCAGCCCCAUAUCAGCUUUUGAUGUGCUUUCCUCACUAAGCUUAAUCAUUUCUAGCUUUCGAUUGAUUGAGUUAGAGACAGAGUUUUGUUCUGUCACCCAGGCUGGAGUGUGGUGGCAUGAUCAUAGCUCACUGCUGCCCAAGUGAUCCUCCCACCUCAGCCUUCUGAGUAGCUAGGACCACAGGUGCAUGCCAUCAGCAGGACUGGCUAAUUUUUCUUUCUUUUCUUUUUUUUUUUUUUUUUUUUUUGGUAGAGAUAGGGGGUGUCUCUCUGUGUUGCCAAGCUGGUCUCGAACUCCUGGAUUCAUGCAGUCAGCCCUCCUUGGUGCCUCAAAGUUCUGGGAUUACAGGCGUGAGCCACCACACCUGGCCUUUAGCUUUUAAGUGAAAGAUGUGAGACUGUUCUUUUACUUGAACGCUUAGAGGCCGUUGUAGGGUUAUUAAGUGGCGUAAUUUCAGUAUUGCUGUGUCUCAGGUAAUAGGGAGGCCCGAGGUGGGAAUGGCCAGUUGGUAGAGCAGUAUCUGUGAAGCACAAUAAAGUGAAAUGCAAUAAAACAAGGUAUAGUUGUAAAAAGGAUGUCACCUCAUGACAGAGGAAGAUAUGAUCAAAAUGCAAGUCACAAAAGUGAGUGAAGAAGUUGUCGAGAUGUCCACAGAAGGAGGAUUUGGUGGUACUAGCAGCAGUGAUGCCCAGCAAAGCCUACAGUCGUUCUGGCCUCGGGUCAUGGAAGAAAUCCGGAAUUUAACAGUGAAAGACUUCCGAGUGCAGGAACUCCCACUGGCUCGUAUUAAGAAGAUUAUGAAACUGGAUGAAGAUGUGAAGAUGAUCAGUGCAGAAGCGCCUGUACUCUUUGCCAAGGCAGCCCAGAUUUUUAUCACAGAGUUGACUCUUCGAGCCUGGAUUCACACAGAAGAUAACAAGCGCCGGACUCUACAGAGAAAUGAUAUCGCCAUGGCAAUUACAAAAUUUGAUCAGUUUGAUUUUCUCAUCGAUAUUGUUCCAAGAGAUGAACUGAAACCUCCAAAGCGUCAGGAGGAGGUGCGCCAGUCUGUAACUCCUGCCGAGCCAGUCCAGUACUAUUUCACGCUGGCUCAGCAACCCACCGCUGUCCAAGUCCAGGGCCAGCAGCAAGGCCAGCAGACCACCAGCUCCACGACCACCAUCCAGCCUGGGCAGAUCAUCAUCGCACAGCCUCAGCAGGGCCAGACCACACCUGUGACAAUGCAGGUUGGAGAAGGUCAGCAGGUGCAGAUUGUCCAGGCUCAGCCACAGGGUCAAGCCCAACAGGCCCAGAGUGGCACUGGACAGACCAUGCAGGUGAUGCAGCAGAUCAUCACUAACACAGGAGAGAUCCAGCAGAUCCCGGUGCAGCUGAAUGCCGGCCAGCUGCAGUAUAUCCGCUUAGCCCAGCCUGUAUCAGGCACUCAAGUUGUGCAGGGACAGAUCCAGACACUUGCCACCAAUGCUCAACAGAUUACACAGACAGAGGUCCAGCAAGGACAGCAGCAGUUCAGCCAGUUCACAGAUGGACAGCAGCUCUACCAGAUCCAGCAAGUCACCAUGCCUGCGGGCCAGGACCUCGCCCAGCCCAUGUUCAUCCAGUCAGCCAACCAGCCCUCCGACGGGCAGGCCCCCCAGGUGACCGGCGACUGAGGGCCUGAGCUGGCAAGGCCAAGGACACCCAACACAAUUUUUGCCAUACAGCCCCAGGCAAUGGGCACAGCCUUCCUCCCCAGAGGACCCGGCCGACCUCAGCGCCUCCUGCAGGCUAGGACACUGGUGCACUACACCCCAUGCCUGGGGGCCGAGAUUCUCCAGCAGAAAGAUGCAAUAUUUUUUGUUUCCUUUUUUUCCAUUUUUUUCUCUAAGGAAUCAAUAUUUCAAUAUGUUGAGUGUGUGUCCAAUGCUAUGAAAUUAAAAUAUUAAAUAACAUAUUUAUGGCAUUUUCUUGAAGAGUGUGGUUGAAGAAAUAUUUCUCCUUUUGUUUUUCUUUUUUUUUUGUUUGUUACUGCCACUUCUUUUUAGGAGCAAAUCUCCCCAGGGGUGUACGGUAUUUCUUGACUCUGGGAACAGCUGCUACCCCCAAGACUUGCCACGUUGUUCUGCCCUCAGAUGGAAUUAGGUGAAUGUGUGUAGCUGCUUUUUCACUCGUGGUCCUCUCCCCAUCCCUUGCUCUGACCCCAGAGCUCUGUGUAUUUGCAUCCAGAGGCCAUGGAAACAUUCUUUGCAUUUAAGAGACAGAUUUAUUCCCUGUGGAGAGUGGGUGGAUUCAUUGCCACACUCUUUUCUCCCAGGGACCCAGGAAACUAGGACUUUGUGUGUUUGCUGCCCACCUCCCUUUUAUUUUUUAAAUGCAUUAAAAACUGUGCUAGUCUCCUUUGCAUGGACUUCAAGCUGCAUGAAAUGCAAUAAAUCUCAUUUUAGAUAA